GUGUCGGGGCUGAUUCUCUGGCUGUGUGGGGCGCACGGUCCCGGGAUACUGGGGACGGCGGGGUGGGAGGGCGCCGUCCUGGGGCCGCGGCGGCCGGGCGGGGGAGAUGGCGGCGCGAUGGAGCAGCGAAAACGUGGUUGUAGAGUUCCGUGACUCCCAGGCAACUGCGAUGUCUGUGGACUGUCUUGGGCAGCAUGCAGUGCUUUCUGGUCCCUAUCCUUCAGGUUUCCUCCGGUGACUGAGAUCGUUGGCUGCUAAUGCUAAAGAGCGACUGGCAUCUCUCUUUAAGUGGGUAGACGGUGGAGGAGAUCAGCCGCAGAUUCUUAUACAUCGUCAAUCUAGAUGCCCCUUUCGAAGGUCACCGAAAGAUCUCUCGCCAGAGCAAAUGGGACAUUGGAGCUGUGCAGUGGAAUCCUCAUGACAGCUUUGCACACUAUUUUGCGGCUUCGAGUAACCAACGAGUAGACCUUUACAAGUGGAAAGACGGCAGUGGGGAAGUUGGCACAACCUUACAAGGCCACACUCGUGUCAUCAGCGACUUGGACUGGGCGGUGUUUGAGCCUGACCUCCUGGUUACCAGCUCUGUGGACACCUACAUCUACAUUUGGGAUAUCAAAGACACAAGGAAACCUACUGUUGCACUGUCUGCUGUUGCGGGUGCCUCCCAGGUCAAAUGGAAUAAAAAAAAUGCUAACUGCCUUGCCACCAGCCAUGACGGCGAUGUGCGGAUAUGGGAUAAGAGGAAACCCAGUACAGCAGUGGAAUAUCUAGCCGCCCACCUCUCCAAAAUCCAUGGCCUGGACUGGCACCCAGACAGCGAGCACAUUCUUGCUACCUCCAGUCAAGACAAUUCUGUGAAGUUCUGGGAUUACCGCCAGCCUCGGAAAUACCUCAAUAUUCUUCCUUGCCAGGUGCCUGUCUGGAAGGCCAGAUACACACCUUUCAGCAAUGGAUUGGUGACUGUGAUGGUUCCCCAGCUGCGGAGGGAAAACAGCCUUCUCCUGUGGAAUGUCUUUGACUUGAACACCCCAGUCCACACCUUCGUGGGGCAUGAUGAUGUGGUCCUGGAGUUCCAGUGGAGGAAGCAGAAGGAAGGGUCCAAGGACUAUCAACUGGUGACGUGGUCCCGGGAUCAGACCUUGAGAAUGUGGCGGGUGGAUUCCCAGAUGCAGAGGCUUUGUGCAAAUGACAUAUUAGAUGGUGUUGAUGAGUUCAUUGAGAGUAUUUCCCUUCUGCCGGAACCUGAGAAGACCCUGCACACUGAAGAUACAGAUCACCAGCACACUGCAAGCCAUGGGGAGGAAGAAGCCCUAAAAGAAGAUCCCCCUAGAAAUCUCCUGGAAGAGAGGAAAUCAGAUCAACUGGGGCUGCCUCAGACCUUGCAGCAGGAAUUCUCCCUGAUCAAUGUGCAAAUCCGGAAUGUCAAUGUGGAGAUGGAUGCGGCAGACAGGAGCUGCACAGUGUCUGUGCACUGCAGCAACCAUCGUGUCAAGAUGCUGGUGAAGUUCCCUGCACAGUACCCAAACAACGCCGCCCCUUCCUUCCAGUUUAUUAACCCCACAACCAUCACAUCCACCAUGAAAGCUAAGCUGCUGAAGAUCCUGAAGGACACAGCCCUGCAGAAAGUGAAGCGUGGCCAGAGCUGCCUGGAGCCCUGCCUGCGCCAGCUCGUCUCCUGCCUUGAGUCCUUUGUGAACCAGGAAGACAGCGCUUCCAGCAACCCGUUUGCACUCCCCAACUCUGUCACUCCCCCCUUACCGACGUUUGCGCGGGUGACCACGGCUUACGGGUCGUACCAGGACGCCAACAUUCCCUUUCCUAGGACUUCUGGGGCCAGGUUCUGCGGAGCAGGUUACCUGGUAUAUUUCACAAGGCCCAUGACAAUGCAUCGGGCGGUGUCUCCCACAGAGCCUACUCCGAGAUCUCUCUCAGCCUUGUCUGCUUAUCACACUGGCUUGAUCGCGCCCAUGAAGAUCCGCACAGAGGCCCCUGGGAACCUUCGUUUAUACAGUGGGAGCCCCACUCGCAGCGAGAAAGAGCAGGUCUCCAUCAGCUCCUUCUACUACAAGGAGCGGAUGUCUCCUCGCUCUGCCCGGCGGCGUUGGUCCAUACAAGCAAUUAACGACUUCCCGAAAUCAAGACGAUGGAAAAGUAAGCGUGAGGGAUCAGACUCUGGCAAUCGACAGAUCAAGGCUGCUGGGAAAGUCAUCAUCCAGGAUAUUGCUUGCCUCCUGCCUGUUCACAAAUCGCUGGGAGAGCUGUACAUAUUGAAUGUGAAUGAUAUUCAGGAAACAUGUCAGAAGAAUGCCGCCUCUGCCUUGCUCGUUGGAAGAAAGGAUCUUGUCCAGGUUUGGUCGCUGGCUACGGUAGCUACAGAUCUUUGCCUUGGUCCGAAAUCUGACCCAGAUUUGGAAACACCCUGGGCUCGACAUCCAUUUGGGCGGCAGCUGCUGGAGUCCCUGUUGGCUCACUAUUGCCGGCUCCGGGAUGUUCAGACACUGGCGAUGCUCUGUAGCGUGUUUGAAGCCCAGUCUCGGCCUCAGGGGCUACCAAACCCCUUUGGGCCUUUUCCUAACCGUUCUUCUAAUCUUGUGGUGUCCCAUAGUCGAUAUCCUAGCUUUACCUCUUCUGGUUCCUGCUCCAGUAUGUCAGACCCAGGGCUCAACACUGGCGGCUGGAACAUAGCGGGAAGAGAGGCAGAGCACUUGUCCUCCCCUUGGGGAGAAUCCUCACCAGAAGAGCUCCGCUUUGGGAGUCUGACCUACAGUGAUCCCCGUGAGCGAGAACGCGACCAGCAUGAUAAAAAUAAAAGGCUCCUGGACCCCGCCAAUACCCAGCAAUUUGAUGACUUUAAGAAAUGCUAUGGGGAAAUCCUCUACCGUUGGGGUCUGAGAGAGAAGCGAGCUGAAGUGUUGAAGUUUGUCUCCUGUCCUCCUGACCCUCACAAAGGGAUCGAGUUCGGCGUGUACUGCAGCCACUGCCGGAGUGAGGUCCGUGGCACGCAGUGUGCCAUCUGCAAAGGCUUCACGUUCCAGUGUGCCAUCUGUCACGUGGCUGUGCGGGGAUCGUCCAAUUUCUGCCUGACCUGUGGGCACGGUGGCCACACCAGCCACAUGAUGGAGUGGUUUCGGACCCAGGAGGUGUGUCCCACCGGGUGUGGGUGCCACUGCCUGCUUGAAAGCACUUUCUGAACCUACAGAAGUUGGGUAUUGUCUGAAAUCCCAGAGGACCCAUAAGUGCCGGUGACAAGCUGUCUGUCAGGGGAGAGGCUCCAGAACCUGGGUUCGUCCCCAGUGAGACCGGAGGAUGAUCCCCCAAGGACUGCGCAGCAUCAGCUCUUGGUGGGCCUCUGCCUUCUCUUCUGUUUGGCCACCUGGUGUGGAUGUCACUGUGUGAAGAUAAGGACAGAAGUGCAGAGCUGCGCUUUGUGUGUUGUCUAUGUCGGCUGAGCUACCAAGGUGGAAGUUUUCAUGGAGAAAAGCACCUGGCUCCAGGGCCAGUGUUACAGUGUUACCCUGUAAGGUGUUAGCCUUAAACCACCGAGCAGCGUUCUCUUGAUGCCAGUGCAGAGACCAGAGUCAGAUGCCCGAGGACAGUGGGUAGGAAUUUCAUCAACAAAUGGACCUAUGGCAUCAUGGCUUUAGAAGCUGGUACAUUUACUGAGCUGAUGGACAGUGGCCUUCUAAAAUAUGACACUUAAAUUGUAAAUAUGCACUGUACUUAAGGAUUCUUAAGAUGUAUUUUUUUGUUAUUUCUCCUCCAGCUGCUAUCCCUUGGCUAAUAAAAUUCUAGUAAUUUGAAAAAAAAAAAAAAGAGAGAAAGUUAAACAACAUUAUGGUGAAUCAUUUUUUACCCUAAUUCUAAUUGAAGGUAGCUAUUUUGAAUAGGACCAAAGUCAGUGCUCCGAUUUUUAAAGGAAAUGCUGAUUUACUUUUGUCAUCUGACAAGAGAAAAUGGAAUUUGACAUUUAAGGUUCUUCCUAGCCCCAAGAGUCUUAUUUCUUCUAGCAAAAGGAGGACAAGAUUGCCGUGCAGCAUGGAUAGAAAAGUCUCCCUGGCCAGGCCCCAUGGCUCAUGCCUGUAAUCCCACACUUUAGAAGGCAAAAGUGAGGGGAUCACCUGAGCUCAGGAGUUCGAGACCAGCCUGGGCAACAUAAGGAGAUCCCAUCUCUGCAAAAAAUUUAAAAAAUAGGCCGGGCACGGUGGCUCAUGCCUGUAAUCCCAGCACUUUGGGAGGCUGAGGUGGGAGGAUUACCUGAGGUCAGGAGUUCGAGACUAGCCUGGCCAACAUGGUGAAACCCCAUCUCUACUAAAAAUAGAAAAAUUAGCCGGGCAUGGUGGCGGGCGCCUGUAAUCCCAGGUACUGGGGAGGCUGAGACAGGAGAAUCGCUUGAACUUGGGAAGCAGAGGUUGCAGCGAGCUGAGAUUAUGCCAUUGCACUCCAGCCUGGGUGACAAGAGUGAGACUCUGUCUCAAAAAAAGAAAAAAAAAAUUAAAAAAAUAGCCGGGUGUGGUGGCACAUGCCUGUGGUCCCAGCUACUUGAGGGGCCGAGGUGGGAGGAUCACUUGAGUCCAGGAGGUUGAGGCUGCAGUGAGCCUUGAUUGCACCGCUGCACUCCAGCCUGGGCAACAGAGUGAGACCCUGUCAAUAAACCAAAGUCUUCCUUGCCUCUGUUCAGAUGGGCUGGGUUCCAGUGAGUGCCCUCACUCUUCCUUUAGGCUCCCUCGCAAACUGCCUGUGUUUGCCUGUGUUCUGAGUAGUUAUAACAUCUGUGUCCACCAAUUCUUCAGAAUGAUUUUCUUUUUUAAAGUUAAAUUUUUUUUUUUUUUUUUUAGAGAGAGAGACAGGGUCUCACUCUGUCACCCAGACUGGAGAGUGGUGAUGCAAUCAUAGCUCACUGUAGCCUCUAUCACCUGAGCUCAAGUGAUCCUCCCACCUCAGCCUCCCGAGUAGCUGGGACUACAGGUGUGCACCACCAUGCCUGGCUAAUUUCAGAAUGAUUUUCAACUUCACAUUUUGUAUGUGCCAGUGAAAAGAAAUCUUUUUUAUUAUUUCUACUGAAAUAUCUAUUUCUGUUUCUUAGAAUUUUACAGUUCCAAGUAGAUUAGCUUAGGGACUAGGACAUGUCUCAUAAUGGGAGAGCAUUGCAUAUUCAUGUGUUUCAAACUCCAGGUCAGGACCCAUUAGUGGAUUGUGACAUUGAUCUAGUGCGGAAAACCAGCAUUUAAAAAAAUGAAAUGGUGUAAGAGAAAAAUGAUCACAAUGUACCAUACAUAGCUAAGGAAAAUGUUUUGUGUAACUUGUUUACGUGUGUGCAGCACAUGUGUGCACAGGUGUAUACCGGAUCAUAGCGUAAAUUCAUUUCUUACUGAAAGUUGUAGUCAAAACAUUUUCACAACACUGUUUUGGAUGAAGCUUAUACCUCGUCCCCUGUGUUACUGGGCACAAAACUUCAGGAUGUAAGAAAGAACUGAGAUCCUGUGCAGUGGAACCAGAGGUUUAGUGCUGGGCUCUGGUCUGAGGUAAGGUGCCAGUGUCUCAGUAGCGUGAGCAGGGCGGGGGAGCCGCUGGGAGGAUGACAGGAGAAGGCCCAGCCGGGAAUUUGCAUACACAAAUUCUGUUGUAAUGGUGAUCACAGAAUAGGUUGGCUGAUUUACACAGAGAGAAAGGAUCUGUUGUGUUCCUCAGUGAAAUCACACCAUUUGCAGAGAGCAAUCUUUUCCUGUUCCCCACUGCUCAAGUUAGUGUAAAAACCUGUCCCUAUCUGUCCCCAUCAAGAAUGAGAUGUUUUUCUUGUUUUAUUGUUGGAGGAACAUUGACUUUCAAAAUUGAAAAACCUUAAUGGUGUGAAGAAAUUUCGAGUUUAAAAUAUUACAUAAUGUCAUCCUUCAAUACGGAAAUUCCUUUUGAAUUUCCAAGUUACCAGAACAAAAGUCUAAUAUUUUAAAAUAUUCAUGUUUGGAAACAGGUUGGUUGUCUGGUUGCGGGCCAUGGCCGAUAUUCUCUCAGCCGCAGAAUAGAUGAUUACAAGCACCUGA